AAUUCUUUCUCCUGGUGUGUCUGCUCCACCGCCCGAGCUAAUCCCCCAAAUCCGGUCUCCUAAGCCGCAGCUGCUUCCCUUCGCAGUGAUGAAUGGCUCAGGGAGGGAAGGUGAAUUCAUAUUUUAAUUACUGAGACGCGGUGCUAAGGGAGCCGGGGAGGGGGCGGAGGGCUCAGCUUUGUUCUAGAGGCGUCGAGGGCACACCCUCCUUACUGGGUCACUUCUCUUUUGCCCUUUACCUGGGGUGGGGGGUGGCGGGGAGUUAAGGUGGGGGUUGCCUUGCUGAGAGUGCCUCUGCUCUCUGCCUUGGGAGAUGAAGGGAUGGGUCGUGGGGGGCGCAAUAUCCCUCUUCUUGUUUAUCAGAGAAUUGCUGGCAUGCCCCAGCACUUUUAAAUAGCUUCCUAGCCUUCCACCCCCGCUGCCGCCCACUCUGAUGAAGGACAUUGCCAAAAUUCGAGACACCUAGGAGUUUGUGGUCUGCAAGCCUGGGGCCCUGGAUUUCUCUUUAUCUUACUUUCUGGCCUGCUCUGAGUCUCCUCUUUCUCUUGGUUCUUCCACAUGUUCAUGCUGUCUCUGACUCACUGCCCCAUUUUUGCCAGAGGUGCAAGGGUUGGAGGACCCCAGGAGAGUAUCUGGCACAGAGAGAUGUGGGGGUCAGGCCAAGGGAAAGGAUCAGCAGGGAGGCCGAGGAACCUCCUAGUGGUGGGGGAGGACGGAUGCUCUAUGGAUUGGCAUCUCUUCUGCUUGGCUCCCACAAAGCUGGCUGGGCAGGGCAUCGUCUGUGCCCCCAGACCGUAAACCAUCUUGGACCUGAGCUGGGAAAAAGCCAGAGAGGAGGAUGGGGAAGAAGCCAGGGCCAACAGCUUGCAGUCAGAUGCAGCCAACUGUGUGGUAGCAGGAGGUUUGUCCAGUGUCCACCCUGCCUCUCCAUCCUAUUCUGGGCUUCUGUUUUUCUGGGGGCUGUUUUUCCAUUCCUUAGUCCCUCCUGGACUAUGGGCAUGGAAAAGGAGGGGGAGGAUGGGAGGGGAGUUCCCAUGAUGAGCUCUGAUGAGUGGGGAGUGGACCCAGGUGCUAGUCCAGACUCCUCCCCCUCAAAUAGACGCAGCAAGGGGACCUGACUUCAGGGAGCCUCCAGCUGGUACUGGAGCCCUCUGCCAAGGGUGAAGGGGUAAAGUCAGGGAAGAGAGUCGACAGGACUCCUGCUCGAGCAAAGCAGAGAGGAGCAGAGACCACAGCCUGGCAGAGGGACUCCCCAGGUACCUGCUGCUGGGGACUCUGAGGGAGGAGUGGGGUUCACAGCGGGCAGGGAUACGGAAAUGGGUUGGAAUUCUCUGCCCCAUGUCCCCCCACUUCAGGGGCUGGCCCGGCAAUCUGCAUGCUGCAGACAGAGCCCAGGCAGCCUCCGGGGCAUGGAGUUGUGCACCUUACAGUGAGGACCCUUUUAGAGACCCUGUUAGAGAAGAGGAAGGAUAACCAGAGCACUUUAGAGCAAAGAUCUGAGCAGAAUAACCAGGCCCUGUUUAUGAUACUUUCUACUCUUAGAUACAAGGACCCAGGAAUCCCACUGAGGCAGCCAGCCCUCGAACACCUCUCGGGAGCCAGGCUACAGCCCCUAGCCCAGCUCCUGGCCAGCUUCAUUAGCUCUCCUUUCCUCUGAUGUGUAGGUUCUGGUUCCUGUGACCUCACUCCCCAUCCUUCCCUACAGUGACAAGCUGAGCAAAAAAAGCCAGGAUUUUCUUAAAUUCCCCAAAGGACCCUGGGGAGGAACGGGUCAUUUAAGGGGGUAUAUUCUGCUGUUUUUAAGAAAGAACAGUCAUUGAAAAGGAAGUGGGGUGAAAAGGAAAGGGGAUCGAUGCACUCUGGGGCCAGAGACCCUGAGCUGCACCUUGACCUGUUUGUGGGGCUGCUACCUGCCUGGCUUGUUUUAGUUGGGAGUUCCUUCCCAGAUUAGCCUUGUUGUGCCUGUCAAUUUCUCCCCAUGUAUUUUUCAAUAAUCAUGGGACUGCUUUGUUGAUCAUACCCUUGACUUAUAUCCCCAGCAAGAGAAGUGCACGUGUGACAAUAACUGAUUACACGGGAAUCCACCUGCCCUCCCUCCCUCCUUCCGGAUCAAGUUAGGAUUCCAGCCCCUUAGGUUUGGGGUCUUAGUGUUAAAUCUUGCCUAAUCUCCUGGUACACUGAAAUGAGGUAAUGAAGGCCCAGAGAGAUGUAGCCACUUGCUUAGGAUGACACAGCAUGUUAGCAUCAGAGCCAGGAAUAGAACCCAGGCCACCUAAGUCCCAGAUUGGAUCCCCGUCUCUCUCUAGGUUUGUCACAGGAGGGAUCCAGAGAUAGCUGCAGGGGAUAGAUCUAGAAAUAUAGUAGUUGUGUCUUGGCUCUAUAUAUAUCCUGGAGGUUGCUCUCUGCUAACUAUAUAUACUCCACCAGAGUGGGUGUGUAAAUGAUGCUGGAAAUCGGGUUAUUAAAUAACCAGCCUACCUACCCAUGCUGACUCAAGCUGGGCCUCCUGCCCAUCCAGCUGGCCAGUGGAAAUGCAUUGCACCUAUUAAUUACAGCUAUUAGCUGUAUUACCGGGACGCUGAGAGGCUGAGGGAGGGGAGAAUCUUGACAGGACUUGGAUCCACCGGGCACUGUGCUUGGUGUGGGCCUUGGCUCUGUCUGGAGAAACACGAAGGAAGUUUUUCCAAAAGGGCAAGGUUGUCCAGACCAGUGGAACUGUCCAGAGAGCCACCAUCUGGGCCAUGCCACAUUCCUCAAAGGCAGUGAAACCACUUUGCACAUGUGCCUUGCUGGGGUAACCCAGGACAUCCUAUGCAAUCUCUAUUGCUUGAGGGGCUGGAGAAGGGAGGCGCCUCAUGCUUCCCUAUUCCAAACCCCUUCCGCAUAGCCCUGUGCCUCCCUCCUUCCCCGCAGCACUUGGGCUUCACUCACCUGCUUGCCCCCAUGUUCUUCCUGGAGAGAGGAGUGAUUCAGACCAGGCCCCGGCCUGACCUCCACGCAGGGCGCUUUCCUUCCUUUGUUCUCAGCUUCUCCGCUUGAGUGGCUUGAGUGCACUUCUGCUCCCUUUCCAUAGGCCCAGGGGCAGAGGAAGGGCAGAGAGGUGAACUGGAAAAAUCUGCAGGUGGUUAAGGCUAGGGAAACCUAAAUGAGCCUUUGGAGAAAGGGAUACUCUUGCAGACUGAAGCUGAGCUCCUGAAGCUCCCUCUCUUCCCCAGCCAGACUGCAACAGAUACCAGAGCGGCCCCUGGCUCCUGCUGAGGGCCGGGUCAGCCAGAGGUGGGGGACAGCGUGUCCAGCUGGGGCAGAUCCAGCCUCAGCCUCUACCUCAGACUUAUGUGCCAGGGAAGAAACCAUGUCUUUACCCUUUUGUAUCUACCUCUCAACCCUUUGCCCAGCAUAGGUGCUAAAUAAAAGAGCCUGUUGGCUAAAAGAACCCUCUUUGCUGUCUCUUCUCUGCAUGGUGAGGAUGGGAUUUGCAUUGCCCUGAGCAGUCAAAGGAAGGGUAUAAUUGCUCCCUAUAGGCUUUCCUAGGGUGUCAGACAACUUGGGGUUGUUAAGGAAGGGAGGAAUCUGACUCGGUCCCAGGUGUCAAAGUAAAGCUACACUGGAUGAAGGGGUCCGCAUUUGGAUGGAGGAGGGCCUGUCGUGUGUGCAACCUGCAGAAGCGAGUGGAAGCCCCCAGCUAGAACCUGGUGUAAGGUGGCACAAGCCGGAGGCUAUUUUAAGCCAGCUUGCUUCCUGUUCCCCAACCACAGAUCUCUGGUGAGUGUUCCCCCAGCCUGGCGUAGGGCAUGCCCCAGUUCACUUUCGCCUGCUUCUGUGGUCUCCACGGCUUCUGCAAAAUGAAGAGGAAGAAGGAGGAAGUUCACAGAGAGCGGGAGACGGCGGUGUGAUCAGAACCAGGGCCCCUCCAUCAAGCCCCCAGCAGGUCCCAGGCCUGAUGGUGCCUGCUUCUGGCUGGGGCUUGGAGCAGGAAGCCGUGUGUGUAUCUUAAGUCUUGAUUUAGCCAGUGCUCUUCUCAGCCUGACUCUCACCCGAGGGCAUCAGCCUCCUGUGUGCCUCUCAUCCUCCUCAUGCCCACACCCAUUAGCUUCCAAUUCUCAGACCUCCUUGGAGAGAGGCCCCAGCCACACAAGGGGGAACCCCAGGACCUGCCGCAUGCCUUCCAGAGACUGAGAAGCCCCAGGGAGGCCAAGGAGUGAAACUUCUUUCCUGCCCUGAGAGCUUCGGGGGACUCUUCUCAGGGUAACCGCAUGAGGCAUGUGCCGCCUUGGGCUAGGAGAGCUGUUGCUAAAUGGGAAACUGGCUGCUCUAGCAGAGAACUUCCAGCAGCCCUGACCCUGGAGAAGGCCUCCAGGGCGGAAGUGUGAGACUCUCCUGGGAUUCCAGGACCUGGGGCAAGAAUCCUUUUCCAGCCCCCUGCCAGCAUCCUCCUGGGCCAGGUGGGGCCAGGCCUGAGGUGGCCAGCCCAGUGAGGAGGAAGGCAGAGGUGGCCAGUGGCUCCGUGGCUCCCUCUGUUCUUGCUCUCCAGAAAGCAGUGUUUCCUCCAGCCCCGGCCCUGACCCACCCGUGUUCAUGAUGCCUGUGCCUCCUUGCCAGCAUCACAGAUGUGGGGAGGCCUGUUCCCCAGGCCCUGACUCCCCUCCUCAGGGACUGUCUUGCCGUGGCCAGACUGAGGGACCCCUUUCCUGGACUGAGCCGUGCCCUCCCUUGAUUCUCCUGUCUCCCCUGCCUUUUUCUUCUCUCCUCAGAAGCCAUAGAGGGGACUGCGUUCAUAUGUGGUGCCUUCAGUGGAAACUCUUAGGGUGGGGGGACCUCUAGGACCUUCCUCGACUUUUUCCCUCAUCCCCCACCCCCGCCAACCUUCCAGCUUCAGCCUCUGCCCUUACCCCCAGCCCAUUUCCAGGAGGUAGGAAGCAAAAGAAAAAAGCAUUUCCUUCCCUCUUUCCUUCUUCCUUCCUUCCUCUCUCCCUUCAUUUUGGUAUAACUUAGCCUUUUGUCUUUAAUCCUGGAGUUCUCCGGGGCUAGAAGACAGGCAGAGACGAAUGCCAGCAGCAGAGAUGCUUCAGGCAGAUUCUGUAAGCCUGUUCUCCCUCAUCAGGGAGCAGCUCAGCCAAGGAGCAAAGUCAGACCCCCUCUAGCUCCCCAGGGACAGAAUAGCCCUUCUGACAGGUAAACAGGUGACCUGGGUAGAGAGGGCAAGGCCCCAAGAUAGGAGAGUCAGGGCUCCCCUUUCCUUGGAAUGUGGGCCUCUCUGGGCAACUAGGGAGGGCAAAAGUCUUCCUCGGCUGGUUCGCCCAAAACCUGGGAGAAGCAAGGGCACAUUCUAUGCUGGCAGCCUCUGCCUGCCCAGCUCAUGCCCACACUCAGGGGCCUUUCCUGGGCUUUGGGCAGAUUGGGUGGGAUUCAGGUUGUCUUUAUGAGGCUUGAGCACAGCUUGAGUUCCUCCUCCCAUCCUCCAACCCCUUCCUUUGCCCCUACCUCCUAGCCCCCACCUUCUACAAUCUGUUAUUUCCUUUUAUAUCCAAAGAAUUAUAAACAGAAGUCCUUCCCUCAAGGGAACAGCAAGAUUCAGCAAUAAAGGCCAGUGGGGUCACAAAGGACAGAAGAAAAACUCCCUGGUUCUUUGUCCUCUUGGAUAGUAGAGGCCUUGGGUGAGGCAAAGAGAUGGGCAGAAAAAGUUACCUUGAUACAGAGGCCAGAGAGCCUCCUGGAGGGCAUGUGUUUCCCUAGCGGUCACCUGCGAGGCUGCAAUCCUAGAAAAGUCACUUCUGUGGCAGAGGAUGAAAUUGUAUCCCCGGAGACUCAGAGAUAUUGGGUGUUAUGUCCUGACCACACAGGCUCACCAGGAGGAAAGGUUAGGAAAGUGGAGAAAGUACGUCCUGGGGAGCGGGUGGCCGAGGAGAGCUUUCCCCUUGUGCGCCUCUCAGGCCUUGGCAGGGAUUGCAGCUGCAGGGGUUUGGCAGUGAGCCCAUCCAGAGAGCUUCCUCCCCCGGGAGAACUCCCUUGGCUCCAGAGGGAUACUAGAUAUCUUGAGCCCUGGCUUUGGGAACAUGGGUGGGGUCCCAAGGUCAAAGUGUUCUGAGUGGAGGUCCAGUUGUCCUCUGCCUCCAAGCCGGCAGCCCCUUCUUCACCCAGGGCUGAGGUUGGGGCCAGCACUGCAGCUGGAAUUGUCUGAGCAGGAGGUAGCAGCUUCUAGCCAGGCACACCCCAACCCCACAUUCUAUUGUCCCUCAGUUUCCUUCUCAGGAAAAUGGGGACUUUGCUCCUUUUAGCAUCUCAGGAAGCAGUCUGGACACCUGUGCCCUCCUCUAGGCCCUUGGAUGAGCCCAGGGAAUAGGGAAAGGCCAAAGCAGCCCCAGCAUUCGCAGACCCUGCGCCCUGGGCCUCUGACUUCGGGCCAGGCUUCUGCUCCUUCUAGGGUUGGCCUGGCUGCCCUGCCUUCCCAUCCUCUCUCCAUGGUUCUCUCCCAGAGACUCCACCUUGAGGUGGGGGCCCUGAGCUCUUGGGGUGAGGGAGGGGCACAUGGGUAGAUGAUUCUGUGGAGGAGAUCAGGCCUCUUGUUCUUGCUGCGUGGCACUGAUUCCUCCUUGCAGAUGGGUGAGGGGGCCAGUUUUCCCCAUCUGUAAAGCGAGGACUUCCCAUGGCCAUUUUCCCUCUUGGGCUUCAGGCUGCUGAAUGGAAGAUCAAGAAGUGUGAAGGGUGCUUGGGGUCCUUGUGACUUGAGUGUUGCCUAGGACCCUGGCCCACAGGACCCAAGGGGCUUCUUGUCUCAGGUUGAAACCUUUUUAUCAGAAUGUCAUUUCCUUCUCUGCUCCCAGGGAAGGGCUUUUUGCAUGUAGCAUAUGGGUUCAUAGAAAUAUAUAGGGAGAUUGUUAUUUUUAGGAAAAAAAAAGAGCAAUAAUUAACUAACUGAAAUACACAUGAAGUGUUAGAGUGGGAUGCAAGGAGCACUGAGCUGGGAGCCAGGUCUCCUGGCUUCUAGCCCUGCUUGGAAACUAAUGACCUAUGUGACCUUAGACUAGUCAUGUCUUAUUUCUGAGACUCAGGUUCCUCAACUAUAAAUAGGGGAUUACAUAAAUUUCCUCUUAAGUCUCCUUUGGAGUCCAGGGCUCUGUGAGUCUGGGAAGUUGAGCCUCAGUGGGGCAUAGGGUUGUGGAACCAGAGGGUCGCAGGUUUCCUCUGCCCUCACAGAUGCACUCCGUGCAGACAACAGACAUAUCUGGAGGGUGGAUGGAAGUGGUAUGGUGGCUCUGAGAAGUGAGAGGGGGAGUGAGAGGGAAAGGCAAGUCACCCAGAGCUUCUGCUAGAAUCUUCCCCUAGCCAGGGCCCAGGACUCCUUGCAGUUCUGCCUCUCUUCCCUCCUACAGCCAGGCCCAAGGGGAGUAAGUCAGUUGGCCUAGACUCUGACUCCAGGUCCUGUCUAGGCCAUCACAGGCGCCACUCUUAUGUACGUUCUCACUUUCUCUCUGUCACAUACACACAGCAUCACCACCACCACCACCACAACCACCUGCAGAUAGAUGCUCAAGUGAUUCUAGAAGAGAUCUCAAGGACUGGCGCUCUGCUCCAGUUAUGUAACCCAUGGGCUUCCCUUUGCACAGCUCCUCAUGUGCUCAUCUCCAUGCUGAUCAAACCACCCCACCUCAUUCCUUGCCUUCUGCAAGGGGAAGUGCCUCAGGCUGGAGUUUGUCCUGUCUACAGACUGAAUAUGCAUUUUGCCCAGUGGCUGGAGAUGUGCUGGUGGUGGAAUGUGCUGGUGAUUGUUUCUGGAUGGAGAGCCACAGCCCCCCAGUGUUCUGCCAUGACUGACUCCUGACCUUGGCAAAUUGCCUCCUCUCUCCCAGCCUCCUCCAUAACAGGUGGCGAUGAGUCCCAUUUCCUCCCUACCUCACAGGAAGGCACGCAUUAUAAAGGGCACACUUAUCAGAUGUGCCCAGAUGUGGCUGGAACUUUUGGAGACAGAUACUUGGUUCACAACUGCAAAGGUGGGCUUUCACCAGAGAAGAAAAUCUCUGGGCUGCUGAGUUCAGUGGGCUCCUUGCAGGCUGGUCCAGGAAGUCUGGUGUUCCUCCUGAAGGUGGCUGCUAUGUCCAGCAGGUGAUCAAGCUGACAGUACCACAAGAACCAAGAAACAGAAUCUGUUCCCAAGGAAUGAAUGUUCUAUCUCUCUGACCCAAAAGCAAGAGCAAGAGAGAGCUGUCACCAUCAUCACCCUGCUCCCAACACAAACACAGCCCCCCAAGUCCAUAUUGCUGACAAGGGUAUCUGCCUUGUCAGGGUGAAUCCUCUGGACCCCAGGCCAUCCCUGGAGUGGUCAGUGCCCACUGUGCCGGGGUUAUUGUGGCCAGUCCGCCUGGGUUCGCUUCUCUAAAUUUCCAUGGGAUAGGAACUAUAGAUCAUGAAGAAGAAACAGGAACCUUGACUCUUCACGGAGGAGCCCAGGAGGUCAGAACCAUCCACCAGGAGGGUGAGCGGUAGCUGCCCAGGGCAUCCCUGGAGGAAGUCGUCAUACUGAGGAAGAAAUUGCCAAAGCCAAGAGCUCCCAGACCUGGGCAGCUCAGGAGCUGACAGAAACCACCCCCCAGGUCUGGAGUUCAAGGGUUUUCCUCGUGGGCUGCUGGUCUGUCUCUUUCCCUUCUGGGGCAGCCGUCUCUCCUCCUUCAGCUCAUUCCCGUGUUCCAUCUGAGGGGCGGGAGGAAGGCAGGAGGGGGAGAUGGCAGGACCCAGACAGAUCCUCAGGACUCUCCCAGCCUCUGUUGCCAUGGCAACACUGCUAUUUUUAUCCCGUUGUUCAUGAUGCUCAAAGCUCUAACUUUCUCUGUUCCAGAGAGGCCAGGCUGGUUUCUGCCCUCAUCCUUUAACACAGCAUCUUCUCCCAGAGGCCUGAGGAUGGGAAAAAGUGAUGGAGAAAAGGGGAACCCCUAAGGUCACCCCUCAGCCAGGGGGAACUGUUUAACAGGGGUUUGUCUCUGCCCUUUUGAGCCUUUGGUUUUCUACCUGGCUCAGGCACCCAGGUUUAUGUUUUCUAGAUCAAAACUCUGCAUGGUCUCCCUGAGAGACUGGAAAAGAGCUGCCAAUCAGGAUGGAUUUUUUCCUACACAGGUAUGACACUGCAGCCACUUCCCUUCUUGGGAAAAUUAAACUUCAUUCUGAAGAAUGUCCUGUUGGUGGUAUAAGCCAACCCCUGCCCUCCUAAAAGGGGAUAGAUAAUUAAAUUUGGUUAAUUAGCAAUCAGAUUCACUGGGGAAUUGAAACCAGUACUUCCCUUUCUUCUGUCCCUCCACCAAAGAACCGGAACAAAUGGCUUCAUGUCUUUGUCCAGUCUUUCUGCCUAAAGCAAAAUAGCAUAUAUUCUCCAGGCUGAAAAGUAGAUUCCUCCUCACCCCUACUCAAGAUGGCCACAUUUCAAUCCAGGCUCUUGAAGACAGGGUCUAAUGAAAGGAUUUCUGUUCUUUCUCUGUCUGUUCCCUCUGGCCCAGCUUCUAGUCCUCUCCUUAUGUCCCCACCUCCAUGGCAGUGGCAAGAGACCCCUGAGAGUCAAUGGUGCUAACGUUCCCCACCUAUAUACCCCUAUGUAGUUUAUCGAGAUUUGAACCCAGCACCUGGGUGGCUGUGUUGGGCGGAUACAUUUCACGUCCUCAAGACCACAACCCUGGCGACAGGUCUGGAUUAAUUCUGUAAAGUAGCAAUCUAUAUCAUGCUAAACUCCUGCACUGAGGUUCUUCCUCGGCUGAACUGACUCGUGGAUGGUUAAGUUUCCUGGGGUGGCUGGAACCCAUUUACUAAGCCUCUAAUUGGUUUCAUUUUGGCUCAAGUUGCAUGGUUUCCCGAAUCUAUGCACCUGGAGUAAGCACUUUUCUGGUUGCCACUGAAAAGCAUGCCGGCAAACGCUGCUCUGUUAAUUGCUGUAAUAAACAGACUUUAUUAUA